AGCAGUUACACUGCGGCGGGCGUCUGUUCUAGUGUUUGAGCCGUCGUGCUUCACCGGUCUACCUCGCUAGCAUGUCGGGCCGCGGCAAGACUGGCGGCAAGGCCCGCGCCAAGGCCAAGUCGCGCUCGUCGCGCGCCGGCCUCCAGUUCCCAGUGGGCCGUGUACACCGGCUGCUGCGGAAGGGCCACUACGCCGAGCGCGUUGGCGCCGGCGCGCCAGUGUACCUGGCGGCAGUGCUGGAGUACCUCACCGCUGAGAUCCUGGAGCUGGCGGGCAAUGCGGCCCGCGACAACAAGAAGACGCGAAUCAUCCCCCGCCACCUGCAGCUGGCCAUCCGCAACGACGAGGAGCUCAACAAGCUGCUGGGCGGCGUGACGAUCGCCCAGGGAGGCGUCCUGCCCAACAUCCAGGCCGUGCUGCUGCCCAAGAAGACCAGCGCCACCGUGGGGCCGAAGGCGCCCUCGGGCGGCAAGAAGGCCACCCAGGCCUCCCAGGAGUACUAAGAGGGCCCGCGCCGCGGCCGGCCGCCAGGCCUCCCCAUGCCACCACAAAGGCCCUUUUAAGGGCCACCACCGCCCUCAUGGAAAGAGCUGAGCCGCUUCAGACUGCGGGGCAAGCGGGCCGCGGCUCCCUUCCCCUCCCCUCCCCUCGCCCGCCUUCGCCGCCCGGCCUCGAGUCCCCGCCCGCCCCCGCUCCCGUCCCGCACCGCCUGCCGCGUCGGCCUCGGGCCCUGCCCUGUCCGCCGUCCGCCCUCCGGUAGGGUUCGGGCCUUCCGGAUGCGGCUUGGGCGCUCUUCGGGGACCUCCGUGGCGCGGAAGACCCGAGCCUGCCGGGGGGAGGCCGGCGGCGCCGCACCUGCCCGCCUCGGCGUUCGUGACUCAGCCGCCCCAUCCCGAGUCGCUAAGGGGCUGCGGGGAGGCCGCAGCACCUUCUGGAAGACUUGGCCUUCCGCUCUGACGCAGGGCCGAGGUGGGCAGUCCAGGCCGAGAGGCCGGCGGCCCUGAAGGUGAGUGAGGCCCUCGGCAGCUGCAGCCGGGGUGUCUGGUACCCCCCCGGCGUGGUGCUUAGCCCAGGACUUUCAGACGCGGCCGCUGGCCGGGAGGCUUUGGUGGGAGAGACGCGAUCGCCGAUUUCGGUCUGGCGCCCCUUCUGCGGCCGGGACCCAGGCCUUUCACAUCAGCUCUCCCUCCAUCUUCAUUCAUAGGUCUGCGCUGGGGCCGGGACGAAGCACUUGGUAACAGGCACAUCUUCCUCCCGAGUGACUGCCUCCUAGGAGGACAUUUAGGGGAGGGCAGAGGCCUGCAGUUUGGCUUCACGGCUGGCUAUGUGGACAGCAAGAGUCGUUUUCGCGGAAGCCGACUGGCAGCCAGGCCUGUCGGGCCCCCCGACGCCGCCCCAUUUCCCUUCCAGCAAACUCAACUCGGCAAUCCAAGCACCUAGAUACCAGCACAAGUCGGUUAAUCCCUGUCUGGACUGAGCCUCCGUUGGCUUCUGAACUGGAAUUCUGCAGCUAACCCUUCCACGACUAGAACCUUAGGCAUUGGGGAGUUUUAGAUGGACUAAUUUUAUUAAAGGAUUGUUUUUUUUUUAAA